ACUCUCCGUAGACAGCUCUGCAGGGAAGUCUGUGACAACCUGGCCAGACAUAGGGCUCACGAUCUGAUCAGAGUCAUGGCACCCCAGACUCUGCUGCCUGUCCUGGUUCUCUGUGUGCUGCUGCUGCAGGCCCAGGGAGGAUACCGUGACAAGAAGAGGAUGCAGAAAACACAGCUAUCCCCAGAAAUCAAAGUCUGCCAGCAGCAGCCUAAACUAUAUCUAUGCAAACACUUAUGUGAAUCUCACCGAGAUUGUCAAGCAAAUAACAUAUGCUGUUCUACCUACUGUGGGAAUGUUUGCAUGAGCAUCCUGUGAGUGGGAGAGUGGGCUGGGAUGUGCAUCCUGCUUCCCAACUCCUCUAUCCAAGACUGUGCCCACAUCCGAAGCACAAGGACCUCAAGUCACCAGCAUAAGAACAUCAACAGGAAUGCCGCCCUCUCUACUGUCUGAACCCCUUGUCCCUGUCAAAUAAACCAGAACAAAUGCCCAGGGA